AGGCGGCGGGCAAGGACGGCGGGCACAGCGCAGCACUCCCCGCUCGUUGGCCCGGGUAUCCCAGCGCGGACCCACGCGAUACGCUGACGCCCCGACGCCGAUCCGGCCGAGCCAAGUAAGGGGGACGGCCCGAGACGGAGAAGGGAGAGAGUGGGAGUUUCCCAGCCCGCAGAACUUUCGAAGUUGAGAAAAGAACCCCUGGAACGUGCGCUCAGCACUGGGAUUUUCUGGACUCAACGAUGACUCUGAAUAAUGUCACCAUGCGCCAGGGCACUGUGGGCAUGCAGCCACAGCAGCAGCGCUGGAGCAUCCCAGCUGAUGGCAGGCAUCUGAUGGUCCAGAAAGAGCCCCACCAGUACAGCCACCGCAACCGCCAUUCUGCUACCCCUGAGGACCACUGCCGCCGAAGCUGGUCCUCUGACUCCACAGACUCAGUCAUCUCCUCUGAGUCAGGGAACACCUACUACCGAGUGGUGCUCAUAGGGGAGCAGGGGGUGGGCAAGUCCACUCUGGCCAACAUCUUUGCAGGUGUGCAUGACAGCAUGGACAGCGACUGCGAGGUGCUGGGAGAAGAUACAUAUGAACGAACCCUGAUGGUUGAUGGGGAAAGUGCAACGAUUAUACUCCUGGAUAUGUGGGAAAAUAAGGGGGAAAAUGAAUGGCUCCAUGACCACUGCAUGCAGGUCGGGGACGCAUACCUGAUUGUCUACUCAAUCACAGACCGAGCGAGCUUCGAGAAGGCAUCUGAGCUGCGAAUCCAGCUCCGCAGGGCCCGGCAGACAGAGGACAUUCCCAUAAUUUUGGUUGGCAACAAAAGUGACUUAGUGCGGUGCCGAGAAGUGUCUGUAUCAGGGACCCUCCAGUGAGACAUUUUCUAUUCAUGCCCUGGGAGGGCCCAUGCCGCAGCAGCAUCCUCUAUCCACUGCAUAUACAGCUGACUUAGUGUUACCUCGAAGAACCAUCCAGCUUGACUGUGUGCUAUGUGGGACUGUGCUCUGCAGUCCCUCUGACCUCUUUCUUUCCUUCCCAGAAGGGAGAGCCUGUGCAGUGGUGUUUGACUGCAAGUUCAUCGAGACCUCUGCAGCUGUCCAGCACAACGUGAAGGAGCUGUUUGAGGGCAUUGUGCGACAGGUGCGCCUUCGGCGGGACAGCAAGGAGAAGAAUGAACGGCGGCUGGCCUACCAGAAAAGGAAGGAGAGCAUGCCCAGGAAAGCCAGGCGCUUCUGGGGCAAGAUCGUGGCCAAAAACAACAAGAAUAUGGCCUUCAAGCUCAAGUCCAAAUCCUGCCAUGACCUCUCUGUACUCUAGGAACCCAGGGUCACCCAGAUGUCCCUUUGAUGGCCGUUGUUGAAGGCCAUUGGGACCAAUAAUCUAUAUUAGAUUGAAUACUUAAGUUAGAUGUGGUUUCCCCCAUUGUAGCAGGGAGCUAGCGUAUUAGCCUUGUGGGCAACAUGAUGCAUGGGAAAUGAAAGAUUUUUGUAAAAAGUCAGUAUUUAUUUCCAGGAAAAGCCUGACCUUGCUAUUUGAACACCCAAGACUCUUUAGAGGAUGUGUUUGGUGUUCACAUGUGUUUCUUCUAUUUUGGAUAGUAGAGAAGUAAAGCUUACAAAGAAUGCCUAGAACAAGAACUUUUCAUCAUUAAAAAUUUUUCCCAGUGUUCUGAUAUGUGACUUUGAGGCCAAUGAGUCAUAAACAAAUAUAAGAAAGCUGUCAAUGAGUUUCUUCAAAGGAGGGAAAACUUUCUACGAAUCUAAGAUCCAUGGAGCUAGAAUUGUAGAACUAGGCUCAUCAGAAUCGUGACUAUUAUUGCUCCAUCAAACUGUGAAAAGAAAUGAUGUGGACCUUGCUGGAAACAAAGGCUUAGCAAACAAUUUUUGUUCAAUGCCCACCAAGACAUAUAGAAUUGGGAACUGAUACAUGUGUCCCUUAUAGGCUCAAAAAUUAUAUCUUACAAUUUCUUAUUUAGGGGGAAAUUAUUUGAAUCAGAUUCUAUUUAGUCAAACCACCUUUUAUGUUUUAUUAUUUUUGAAUUCAUGGAGCCAUCAUAAAAAUAUUUUUAAAAUCAGAAUUAUUGAUACCCUGUAGUGCAAAAUGUCAAUUUUUAAUGUAUAAUCAGAAGUCUGAAUUUUUAUAAAACAUAUAGCAUAAAAACUUCCAGUACUUUGGUUGACCCUUGUAUGUCACAGCUCUGCUCUAUUUAUUAUUAUUUUGCAAAAUAACCAUUUUAACAUUUGAUAAAGCAUAUUUAUGAACAUAUUUCUUAAUAAGAAAAAUAUCCAUUUUAUUACCAUUUUCUAUCUUUUUCAAAAUAUGCAAGUUUUUACCUAUAUGUCUUAUAAUAAAAGAAAUAAAAUAUUUGAAAAAA